GUCCCGGCGAUGUGUGGCGCUGAGGCGGCGGCGGGAGCAGCGGCGCCGAGCUCUGCUUCGGCUUCGGCUUCGGCUUCGCGGCGGUGCAGGCGGCGGAGGCGGAGGCGCAGGCUCUUCUUUAGGACCUGGCGAGCCCAGGUCUAAGCGGCGGCCCCGCGAGGCCCUUGCACGGCGCCCCGGGUCGAGGCCCUCCCCGCCUCGCCCUACCCCAGGAGCCUGCCUCCCCAGCUGGGGAUGAGGCUAGGAGGCGGCCGCGUGGGGCCCAGCACAAAGACCUGUCCCCAGGGGCCGCCGCCUCCGCCGCUGCUGCUGCCGCCAGCCUAGAGCCGCCCGCCGAAGCAGAGCCGGCGCCGGGGUCCUCAUCCCCACCGGUCCCGAGGGGCGGCUGCUGCCCGUCGCCACGAGGCCCAGGGGCCCGAGUGCCGAGCCCUUUGCUCCCUCGGCCGCGCGGGGACAGGGCUGCUGAGCAGCCUCCGCCUCUCCCGGCUGUGGGGGCCCCACUGAGUAUGUCGGAGGAGAGCGACAUGGACAAAGCCAUCAAGGAAACUUCCAUUUUAGAAGAAUACAGUAUCAAUUGGACUCAGAAGCUGGGAGCUGGAAUUAGUGGUCCAGUUAGAGUCUGUGUAAAGAAAUCUACUCAAGAACGGUUUGCGCUGAAAAUUCUUCUUGAUCGUCCAAAAGCUAGAAAUGAGGUACGUCUGCACAUGAUGUGUGCCACACACCCAAACAUAGUUCAGAUUAUUGAAGUGUUUGCUAACAGUGUCCAGUUUCCCCAUGAGUCCAGCCCUAGGGCCCGACUCUUAAUUGUAAUGGAGAUGAUGGAAGGGGGAGAGCUAUUUCACAGAAUCAGCCAGCACCGGCACUUUACAGAGAAGCAAGCCAGCCAAGUAACAAAGCAGAUAGCUUUGGCUCUGCGGCACUGUCACUUGUUAAACAUUGCGCACAGAGACCUCAAGCCUGAAAAUCUGCUUUUUAAGGAUAACUCUUUGGAUGCCCCAGUGAAGUUGUGUGACUUUGGAUUUGCCAAGAUUGACCAAGGUGACUUGAUGACACCCCAGUUCACCCCUUAUUAUGUAGCACCCCAGGUACUGGAGGCGCAAAGAAGGCAUCAGAAGGAGAAAUCUGGCAUCAUACCUACCUCACCGACGCCCUACACUUACAACAAGAGCUGUGACUUGUGGUCCCUAGGGGUGAUUAUCUAUGUGAUGCUGUGCGGAUACCCUCCUUUUUACUCCAAACACCACAGCCGGACUAUCCCAAAGGAUAUGCGAAGAAAGAUCAUGACAGGCAGUUUUGAGUUCCCAGAGGAAGAGUGGAGUCAGAUCUCAGAGAUGGCCAAAGAUGUUGUGAGGAAGCUCCUGAAGGUCAAACCGGAGGAGAGACUCACCAUCGAGGGAGUGCUGGACCACCCCUGGCUCAAUUCCACCGAGGCCCUGGAUAAUGUGCUGCCUUCUGCUCAGCUGAUGAUGGACAAGGCAGUGGUUGCAGGAAUCCAGCAGGCUCACGCGGAACAGUUGGCCAACAUGAGAAUCCAGGAUCUGAAAGUCAGCCUCAAACCCCUGCACUCAGUGAACAACCCCAUUCUGCGGAAGAGGAAGUUACUUGGCACCAAGCCAAAGGACAGUGUCUAUAUCCACGACCAUGAGAAUGGAGCCGAGGAUUCCAAUGUUGCCUUGGAAAAACUCCGAGAUGUGAUUGCUCAGUGUAUUCUCCCCCAGGCUGGUAAAGGAGAGAAUGAAGAUGAGAAACUGAAUGAAGUAAUGCAGGAGGCUUGGAAGUAUAACCGGGAAUGCAAACUCCUAAGAGAUACUCUGCAGAGCUUCAGCUGGAAUGGUCGUGGAUUCACAGAUAAAGUAGAUCGACUAAAACUGGCAGAAAUUGUGAAGCAGGUGAUAGAAGAGCAAACCACGUCCCACGAAUCCCAAUAAUGACAGCUUCAGACUUUGUUUUUUUAACAAUUUGAAAAAUUAUUCUUUAAUGUAUAAAGUAAUUUUAUGUAAAUUAAUAAAUCAUAAUUUCAUUUCCACAUUGAUUAAAGCUGCUGUAUAGAUUUAGGGUGCAGGACUUAAUAAUAGUAUAGUUAUUGUUUGUUUUUAAGAAAAGCUCAGUUCUAGAGACAUACUAUUACUUUAGGACUGUGUAGUUGUAUAUUUGUAAGAUGACAGAUGAUGCUGUCAAGCAAUAUUGUUUUAUUUGUAAUAAAAUAUACAAAAAUCACUUGCCAGCAGUAGAAAAAGGACCGACUAUACCGACCUUUCUGAUUAGUAAACAGUUGAAUCAAGGACUCUGGAUUCUGGUUUCAAUUGCCCUGUGUGUUUAUUUUCCACACCAUUGCUAGAUUAGCUCUACUGCCAAGACAUUUUUGUGGCUGUCAUUGCAGACUGCUUGCUGGAACUCACAGGAGGCACACUUGAGCUUGGGGAGCCAACUUCCAUGAUGGAAGAAGAGGGAGGUGAGCCCUCAUUUCUCCUGCCCCCUAAUUCCCAAGAGAAAAGCAGGAACAUUUCCUUUUUGUCAUAUCUGUUAAAAGGGUACUGGUGUGUUUCUUAAAUCUAACAGGGUUUUCUUUUGGGUUUAUUCUUUUUUUUUUUUUUUUUUUGAGACAGAGUCUUGCUGUUGUAGUGGAGGCUGGAGUACAGUGGCACUAUCUCCGCUCACUGCAACCUCCGCCUCCCAGGUUCCAGUGAUCCUCCCACAUCAGCCUCCCAAGUAGCUGGGAUUACAGGUGCCCGCCACCACGCCUGGCUAAUUUUUGUAUUUUUAGUAGAGACAGGGUUUCACCACGUUGGCCAGGCUGGUCUUGAACUCCUGACCUCAGGUGAUACGUCUGCCUUGGCCUCCCAAAGUGCUGGGAUUACAGGCGUGAGCCACUGUGCCCGGCCUUGGGUUUAUUCUUUCUUUAUAUGUUUGUUUGUUUGUUUGUUUUGAGAUGGAGUCUUGCUCUUAUCACCCAGGGUGGAGUGCAGUGGCACGAUCUCGGCUCACUGCAACCUCUGUCUCCCAGGUUCAAGUGAUUCUCCUGCCUCAGCCUCCCAAGUAGUUGGGAUUACAGGCACCCGCCACCAUGCCCGGCUAAUUUUUGUAUUUUUAGUAGAGACAGGGUUUCACCAUGUUGGCCAGGCUGGUCUCGAACUCCUGACCAUCCACCUCAGCCUCUCAAAGUACUGGGAUUACAGGCAUGAGCCACCAAGCCUGGCCUAUUCUUUAUAUGUUUAACCGGAGCUUCCCUUUCCCCUUCCAGGAGGUCCUGCUUUGUCCUUUCCCCUUCCCUGCAGCCUUCACCAGCUCCAUUACUCCUUAUUUCUGUUCCCUGUUCCUCUGGUCCUGUUUUUGGAAUAACUUGUCCGAGAAAUUUACAUAUAAUUAAUUGAAGUGGGACUAUUGGAUUAUCAUGUAAGAUGAUCCAGUUUUGGUUUUUUUUUUUAUAAGGCUGCCCUGUUUCUCUGUAAUAUGUCUGUCUGGGUUUUGUGUUGGCAUCCUCUGGGCUGCAUUUAUCUUGUUUAUUACCCUUCAUUUUCAGGAAGCAUGGUUUUGGCCCCGAGAGCAGCUGUUUGAAGGAAAAAUAAGGCUAGGUCCUUUUUUAGUUUUCUGUUGUGAGUAUGGGUUUCCAUAACAAACCAAUUUUCGUGUAUAUGUGUGUGUGUGUGUGUGUGUGUGUGAAGCAGUUUUUGGUGGGUACUUACGUUGGUACAUAGAAAAGCUGGCAGGUAGACUCCAGCUCGCAGAGCAGAGGGAGAGGAUAGUCAUCUGUUAUUCAAUUUUUUCUCAUCUCAUUCUCUUCGAUCAAAAUUGAUCUCACCAGCAACUUAUUUUCUAACUCCUCCACUGUGCUGAGUAAUUCCUCCACCCUGAAUCUUCAGGGUGACAUUUGGUUAGUAUGCCCUGUAUGUGUGUGACUGCCUGUGGGAAUAGAUGAUAAAAAACAAGUGUCUUAAGAAUUACCUUAUUACAUUGCUUCCUUUUUUUUUUUUUUUUUUUUUUGAGAUGGAUUCUUGCUCUGUCGCCCAGGCUGGAGUGCAGUGGCGCGAUCUUGGCUCACUGCAAGCUCUGCCUCCCAGGUUCACACCAUUCUCCUACCUCAGCCUCCUGAGUAGCUGGGACUAUACAGGUGCCCGCCACCGCGCCCGGCUAAUUUCUUUUUGUAUUUUUAGUAGAGACAGGGUUUCACCGUGUUAGCCAGGAUGGUCUUGAUCUCCUGACCUCGUGAUCCGCCCACCUCAGCCUCCAAAAGUGCUGGGAUUACAGGUGUGAGCCACUGCACCCAGCCUACAUUGGUUCCUUUUUAUCUUGGAGAAUUUAAUUGAAAGAUAUUUUUUGAGAUAAAGUUCACUAAUCUUAGGUGACUGAUAACUGUUAUAAAUGGAUUUCCUGUAAGGAGAAUAUGUCUCCCCCCCACCCCCCACCCUGCUGCCACCAAGACAGAGUCUCGCUCUGUCCCCCAGGCUGGAGUGCAGUGGCUUGCUCUUGGCUCACUGCAACCUCUGCCUCCCAGGUUCAAGCGAUUCUCGUGCCUCAGACUUCCAAGUAGCUGGGACUACAGGCACACACCACCACGCCCAGCUAAUUUUUGUGUUUUUAGUAGAGACGGGGUUUCAUCAUAUUGGCCAGGCUGGUCUCAAACUCCUGACCUCGUGAUCCGCCCACCUCGGCCUCCCAAAGUGCUGGGAUUACAGGCGUGAGCCACCGUGCGCGACCUGAAUACUUUUCAUGAUGGCAAAAUCUCACCGGCAACAGAAGAAAAACCAAUGUUUUUAAAUUUACUGACCAGAAAACUUGACUGAGAGUUGAAUUAAGUGCCUGUUGUUGUGUUUUUCAGUGAAAUGCAAAUCUUACAGAUCACUUCUUACAGUUAGGAAUACUGCACUUGUUUGUGUAAUAUUAGAACAACUGUAGUUUUCCUAUCUUAGGGCAGAGGUUCAGUAUUCCAUGGGGAGAAAAAAACAGUAAUUAUCUUUGUUACUCUUCUUCUUUAGAGGAAUAUUCUAGCAUAUCCAUUAUAUCCAUAACUUCUUAAAUUUGUGACUUGGGUGUCUUCUAAAAAGGCUCAGGAUGAUUAUUUUUUCCUUCAGUGUAUGCUGAAUUUUAGGUGCGAUGGAAAAGGUAUCCAAAGUGAUACUCCCUUUGACUCUGAGCAUCAGUUGCCCGUGUUUCAGUCACUUCAAGCUGAAUUCAUGCCCUCAAUGUAAGUGCUGUGUCCAGACACAUCCAAAUGAGCACCAAGCUGGAAGUUUGUGAACACUCUGGAGGAUGCCCCAGCUGUUGUAAUGCAACAGCAUACCUUGAAAAAAAACAGUAGCUCCCAAGGGACUCAGCAUGGCUUGGUCUUCGAAGUGGAGUUUUGUUUGUGUAUUCCUAGUCCAGCAGUAAAUUCUGCUUUAACAUAACUGUCAGGUUUGCUACUCGAAAUUUGCACAUAACUGGAAGUGAAACGAUAUCUUUCUCAUAUUUUUUGGCCUAACAAACACCUAUACCUGUGGAAACAUAACACUGUAAAUAUAAUUCUUAUAAAGCAGCAGGUUAUGCUCUCCUGUUUGCCUACAUGAUUUAUUAACCUUCUGCUUACUAAAGCCAUUACUGGUCAAUCAGAUACUUUUAGACUUUACCACAGUUAUAAAAGUCAGCUUGAUGUAGUAAAAAAACUUGUCUCUCUCUGACUAAUAUGUAUGAAUAUAGGAGAAUCCCAGUCUGAAUUUACUGUUUGAAACAUAGAUGAGGCUCAGCGUGGUGGCUCAUGCCUUUAGUAAUCCCAGCACUUUGGGAAGCUGAGGCGGGCAGAUCACCUUAGGUCAAGAGUUCAAGACCAGCUUGGCCAACAUGGUGAAAUGCCGUCUCUACUAAAAAUACAAAAAUUAGCCAGGCAUGGUGGCACAUGCCUGUAAUCCCAGCUGCUCGGGAGGCUGAGGCAGGAGAAUUGCUUGAACCUGGGAGGCAGAGGUUGCAGUGAGUGGAGAUCGCACCAUUGCACUCCAGCCUGGGUGACAGAGCAAAACUCCGUCUCAGAAAUAAAAAAGAGACGUGAUCCUGCUAUGUUGCCCAAGUUAGACUCAAGCUCCUGGGCUCAAGCAAUCCUCCUGCCUCAGCCUUCUAAGUAGCUGGGACUACAGGAGCAAACCACUGUGCCUGGCAGGAAUUACUCUUUAAAAAGAGUUUAUGUUGCUUGUAUUCAUUUGAGAAAAAAUGAGUUGAAGAAAUGGUAAUUGUUGGUCAAAGAAGCCAAAAGAUUUAAAUAAGGUCUUGUGUGUGGGUAUGUGUAUGUGCAUGUAUUUAUUGAAGAAAAUAAGUUUCAAUUUGAGAAUUAGAAAAUUGGAUAUUUCAUUUUAAUUAUUUAUUUAAAGAGUAGAGUGUUCUUCCAUUAUUGAAUCUUCUUUUAUCCCACCAAAUGGCUUAACCUAAUUUGCGCUGCCUAUUUUGGUUAAGAAACAGGGAAACACCCUAAAAUCUGUGAUAAUUUUCAAAAUACAAUUUUAAGAAGCUUUGCGCUUACAUAAAUCACAAGAAAUACAGCUGGAAAUCAUUUCACUUUUCUUGCUGUAAAUUUUUUUAGUGGGUUUGUGACAGUAUAAAUUUUCUUGCUAGAUGCUAAUGAUACAUUGUAUUAUCUGUAUUAGGAAUUAAAUAUUUAAUAGGAAUAGUGAAUAAAUUGAUCUGCUCUCAUGCUGUUAUCUAAGAUCUUAUGCUACCAUUACAUUCCUUUCUGUAGUCGUAUCUCAUAUUUGAAAGGUCUCAUGUUGUAAAUAUUUGACUUGCUGUAAAAUUAUACAAGAUAAAAAAUGUAGAGUUUUAUUUUUCUUCAUCUAGAAUGCACAGAAUAACUGCGUAAGGAAUGGGUGCAUAGGGCUUCUUUUCCUUUUAAAUUUGUACUGCUAAAUACACCAAGGAAAUUGACAUCAAAACCAAAUUCAAGGACUUCCACAGACAUUUCAGGUCAAUUUUAGUUCCAAACCGAAGAAAUCUUUUAAAAGUUCUUAUAUAGCCCAGUUUUCUUUUCUUGAUGAAAUGUUAACUAGACACCUGGUUAGUCAGCUUUUAUUUUGACCCCACAGUUUUUUUUUUGAGACGGAUUCUCACUCUGUUGCCCAGGUUGGAGUGCAAUGGUGUGAUCUCGGCUUACUGCAACCUACGCCUCCUGGGUUCAAGCGAUUCUCCUGCCUCACCUUCCUGAGUAGCUGAGAUUACAGGCGCCUGCCACCACGCCCCGCUAAUUUUUGCAUUUUUAGUAGGGACAGGGUUUCACCAUGCUGGCCAGGCUGGUCUCGAACUCCCGACCUCAGGUGAUCCGCCUGCCUCGGCCUCCCAAAGUGCUGGGAUUACAGGGGUGAGCCACCGUGCCCGGGCCCCACACUUUGUUUUUAUGUUAGGGCAGUUGGAGGAACUGAACUUUGAUCCUGAUCCUUUAUAUACUCCCAUGGUGAAACUUGAGCCCAUUUUACUUAACACAAUAUAUCCGUGCAUUAGGAAAACUUGGUAGAGAAGAUUAUAUGCAGAUAUAAAAUAUCUAAACUCAUUUGUUAUGAACCAACGAUAAUGAGGGAAAACUUGGACAUCCACAUACAGAUUUUCUUGAAUUAAAGAAAAAAACCAGACACUGACAAAGGAGAGCUGAACUGAUAAAUGGUACCCUGAAAACUGCAGAAAUGAGGGAAAGAGGCAGUGGGCCACAAAGAACUUUGUCCUUUUCAGAGAUCCCCAGAGAAGCCCUGCCCCCUUCCCCCCACCCCCUGACAGAAUGUUGUGUUUCAAAGAAUGAGCAGAUUAAUGGAUAUCAAGUUGUGUGGCCUGAGCUGAGGAUAAAGAAUAAUUUGCCUGAGGAGUUACAGUACUGGCUGGAUCACUACAGGCCUUCUACUUGGAAUAUCUUCCCAUGAAAGUAAAAGGAAUAUAACUAAGGAAGAUUAAAGUUGUUGCUGUUGGAAGGAAGACAUACUAAAGAAACUGCCGAAGGCCAGGAGAGAAGCAGGAAGAGAAACACGGCUUGAAGUUCUGUAAGAAUCAGAGUUGGGCAAGAACUGCCAAUAAGGGAGCCAGCGUAGAUCUGAGUACUAAACACCUGAGCCUCCGAGGGUUUGUGUGCGAGGGAGAGCUCUGCUGAUGGACAUAGGCCCAGAAUCAUUAACUGAUUUAUUUGGGCCAUGUCACUGGUGGCAUUAUUAAAAGACUCUGCCAACAUCCUGCUUUAUGGAAAAACCAAGUGGCCUUGGAAGAGGCUAAGAUAAAGUUUCAAACUUGGGCUCCACAGAAGUGGAACUUAAGGCUGGGGCUAGUACCAGGACCUUCAUGUAUCAGGUUAGAGAUUUUGAUGCUUUUGGUGAUUUUUGUGCCAAGCAUGUACUGUCACCUGGGAUCAAUCUAUUACUCUUUCUAUGAAAUAAUUAUUCCAAAGAGGCUGACAGUCCAGGGAGGAGAUAGCCCAGUGGAAGGACUGUCCUACUUGUUACUUAUGCAAGGCCAGAAGCACCUGGUUCAUCUGAAGGUGAAGAGAAACCAUUUUGUGAAUAACUUUCCAGUCUACAGUUACCACAAUGGCCUCCUGGGGCAAGAAUCGCCUUUCAUCUCACAUGACUGCCACUAUGAAGGCUACAUAGAAGGAGUGUCAGGUUCUUUUGUUUCUGUCAACAUCUGUGCAGGUCUCAGGGGCACAUCCUCCUGAUUAAGGAGGAAAAAUCUUACAGCAUUGAGCCCAUGGACUCUUCAAGACGGUUUGAACAUGUGUUAUACACCAUGGCACAUCAAGCGUGAGUCUCCUGUGGUGUCUACUAGCUGGCAACAAGGGAGCAGGAAGCCUCAUGAUCUACAGGCACUGUCCUACUUGUGGUCACACAAAAAGUACGUGGAGAUGUUUGUCGUGGUCAACAACCAGCGGUUCCAGAUGUGGGGCAGUAACGUCAAUGAGACGGUCCAGACAGUAGUGGAUGUCAUUGCUCUGGCCAACAGCUUCACUAGGGGAAUAAACACAGAGGUGGUGCUGGCUGGAAUGGAGAUUUGGACCGAGGGGGACCUAAUAGAUGUCACAGUGGACUUGCAAAUCACACUCAGGAAUUUCAAUCACUGGAGACAAGAGAUGCUCUUCCAUCGUGCAAAACACGAUGUUGCCCACAUGAUCGUUGGGCAUCACCCUGGACAGAAUAUGGGCCAGGCCUUUCUCAGUGGUGCCUGCUCAAGCGGUUUUGCGGCAGCUGUUGAAUCCUUCCAUCAUGAAGAUGUGCUGUUGUUUGCAGCCCUGAUGGCCCAUGAGCUCGGGCACAACCUGGGUAUUCAGCACGACCACUCGGCCUGCUUUUGUAAAGAUAAGCACUUUUGCCUCAUGCAUGAAAAUAUCACAAAAGAAAGUGGCUUCAGCAGCUGCAGCUCUGACUACUUCUACCAGUUCCUUCGAGAACACAAAGGGGCCUGCCUAUUUAACAAGCCACGGCCCAGGGGCCGCAAGCGUAGGGAUUCUGCCUGUGGAAAUGGUGUGGUGGAGGACACGGAGCAGUGUGACUGUGGUUCUCUAUGUCAGCAUCAUGCAUGCUGUGAUGAAAACUGUAUACUGAAGGCGAAAGCAGAGUGCAGUGAUGGUCCAUGUUGUCAUAAGUGUAAAUUUCACCGUAAGGGAUAUCCUUGCUGUCCUUCUAGUCGUUCCUGUGAUCUCCCAGAAUUUUGCAAUGGUACAUCUGCAUUAUGCCCCAACAACAGGCAUAAGCAAGAUGGCUCAAAAUGUCAUACAAUUUACGAGUGCCUUAAAGUUCAUUGUAUGGACCCUAAUAAUCAGUGCUUACAAUUAUAUGGAUAUGGUGCAAAAUCAGCCUCACAAGAGUGUUACAAUUCAAUGAACAGCAAAGGGGACCAAUUUGGAAACUGUGGCAUUUCUACCAGUCCUGGGUCACAAUAUGUUCGGUGUUCAGAUGGUAAUAUAUUUUGUGGGAAACUUAUAUGUUCAGGUAUUACAGGCUUACCAAAAAUCAAUCUCCAACAUACAAUGAUUCAGGUCCCUCAGGGAGAUGGCUCAUGUUGGAGCAUGGAUGCCUAUAUGAGUACUGACAUUCCUGAUGAAGGAGAUGUGCACAAUGGCACUUACUGUGCACCAAACAAAGUCUGCCUGAAUUCCGCCUGCACAGAUAAAACCCCAGUGAUUUCUGCCUGCAACCCAGAAAAAACGUGUAAUGGGAAGGGAGUUUGUAAUGAUUUAGGGCACUGCCACUGUAAUGAAGGGCAUGCCCCCCCUGACUGUGUUACUGCAGGAAGUGGAGGUAGUGUGGACAGUGGCCCUCCUGGUAAGCUAGGUGGGACACCUUCAGGAGAAGGUGAAAAUCACAAUAUGACUCAUUCCAGACGUGAAGAACAUGCUGUAGACAUGAUGAUAUUAUCAUUCAUUAUACUUUUUAUAAUAUUAUUAUUAAGUACAAUUAUUUGAUCUGCUUGCUUAAAAAAUCACCAGAGGCUGCCCCGGCAGAAGCUCCUCCAGCAGUGGCUCCACCACCGGCCCCAGAAAUAAAGCCAGAAGCAGCAGAAGUGGCCACAGAAGAAAAAGAAGAGAAGGAGGAAGAAAAAGAAGAGGAGGAGGAGGAAGAAGAGGAGGAAGAAUCAGAUUCCUAAGGUUAGAAAUAGGGAGAUGAAGCCAAGUAUAUCAAACUCCUCAAGUACUGAGUGGGAAUGAGAUGUUUGGUGAAGUAGAAAUAGAUAGCUUUAGUGGCUCUGACUCAGAUAUACUGAUGUAGAAGGAAGGAUUCUUUCACUUUUAUUAUUUAUUUUGGUAAUUAAAUUUACAUUAAUUUAAUAUGUUAAAUAUUUUAGUACCUUUUGCUUUUUCACAUUUCAUUUGAACCAUUAACAUGCAUCUUUGGACAUCAAUGUCCUUGUCUUUUUGGCCCAAUUGUUUUAGUCACCAGAAACUUUUUCAGGACAUGCUAUCUUCUAUUUGUUUGACAUACAGAAUCAUAUGUACCUGAAUUUAUUACUAACUCUGGGAUUUUCAUUUUAAGUAACAACUACCUAUUAUGUGAGGACAGUUGUUUAUGUGAUUGGUUGUUCUAACUUGCCCUAUAAAUGUGCAUUCAUCAAAGGAGAAGUUUUUAAAUCCAAAAACAAAUAAAACCCGAUUCAUAUUAGACAA